AGCCACACUGGGAAAACAUUGGAGCUUGGUCUGCCAUCCUGAACUGUGGUUCCCCUGCCUCCCAGCCCGGCUGUGAGUGCUCAGCGACCCUGACAGGCUGACAGGUACAGUCUGCCGGGCUUUCCUACUGUCCCUGGCAGCCCCAUGCUUACUCUGCGGCCCAGAUCCCAGCUCUGUGUCCACCUGUUCCUUCUCCUGGGUUCCCUUCCCCCACAGUUCCCAGCCAAGCCAGAGCCCCCCACUGCAGAACUUCCUCCACUCCCUCCCACUUCCUCCCGGUUAGAACAGGACCAGGAGGGAGGUGCCGCUCAGAUUCUGGCAGGACCGCUGGCGGGCAGGCAGGGGACAGUUGGGCCAUAUGGUGCUCUUCCCAGUCUGGUUCCUGUACAGUCUGCUCAUGAAGCUGUUCCAGCGCUCCACGCCAGCCAUCACCCUCGAGAGCCCGGACAUCAAGUACCCGCUGCGGCUCAUCGACCGGGAGAUCAUCAGCCAUGACACCCGGCGCUUCCGCUUUGCCCUGCCGUCACCCCAGCACAUCCUGGGCCUCCCUGUCGGCCAGCACAUCUACCUCUCGGCUCGAAUUGAUGGAAACCUGGUCGUCCGGCCCUAUACACCCAUCUCCAGCGAUGAUGACAAGGGCUUCGUGGACCUGGUCAUCAAGGUUUACUUCAAGGACACCCAUCCCAAGUUUCCCGCUGGAGGGAAGAUGUCUCAGUACCUGGAGAGCAUGCAGAUUGGAGACACCAUUGAGUUCCGGGGCCCCAGUGGGCUGCUGGUCUACCAGGGCAAAGGGAAGUUCGCCAUCCGACCUGACAAAAAGUCCAACCCUAUCAUCAGGACAGUGAAGUCUGUGGGCAUGAUCGCGGGAGGGACAGGCAUCACCCCGAUGCUGCAGGUGAUCCGCGCCAUCAUGAAGGACCCUGAUGACCACACUGUGUGCCACCUGCUCUUUGCCAACCAGACCGAGAAGGACAUCCUGCUGCGACCUGAGCUGGAGGAACUCAGGAACAAACAUUCUGCACGCUUCAAGCUCUGGUACACGCUGGACAGAGCCCCUGAAGCCUGGGACUACGGCCAGGGCUUCGUGAAUGAGGAGAUGAUCCGGGACCACCUUCCACCCCCAGAGGAGGAGCCGCUGGUGCUGAUGUGUGGCCCCCCACCCAUGAUCCAGUACGCCUGCCUUCCCAACCUGGACCACGUGGGCCACCCCACGGAGCGCUGCUUCGUCUUCUGAGGGCCGGGCACGGUCACACGGCCACCCGCCCCGCGCACCCCACGCCCUGUUCACGCUCACCCAGUCACCUCCCCACAUCGCACACUGGGGCCCCGGGUUCAGCCUGGCCUGCCCGUGCCCUGGUGAAUCACCUGGCUGAGCAGUUCCCCUGGAGCCCCUUCGGGAGCAGGGCUGUGUCCCAGAUGGGCCACGGCUGAGCCUUCAGAGUACGUCCUGCCUGGCACUUACUGGUCCUUACCAGAGACGCCCAGCCCCAUCCCUGUCCUCAUGACCCCUCGUCCACCCCCCACACACACUAUAAGGCUGAGGGCUGCCAGCAGCCCCGUCUGCCCACCAUUCCCGGCCGUGGACCAUAGUCGGGAUGUCAGCAGACACACAUGGGCAGCCCAAAGCUGCAGGUGCCAGGGCCCACCCCAGCCUCGCCUGUCACCCCCACUCCCGCCUCAGGGCCAGGCCCAGGCCUCACCACCUGACGCUGCAUGAGACAUUGACACCAGAAAGCCCUCUUGGGGGCACUGCUCCCUACCCCAGGGCCCUGGCCAGCCGGGAGCUUGGCUCUCCUCUGGCUAGAGUGGGAAGAGGGGGCUGGCCAUGGGGCCCUCCCAGAACCUCAGCAUUUCCUUCCAGCCCAUCCAAACACUGAGGCAGCCUUGGGGAACCCCGAGCUGGGGGGUUGGCAGCCCACUGCACCGCCUCAGGGUUUUGGGGUCCUGGGCUGGGGCCACCAUCCCUGAUGGCAGAACUCCCACAACCACAUGUAUUUAUUCCUCUGUCCUAAACCGUCCCCUCCUUCCCUCACCCCCAGCACAGGGGGAUUCUGAGCAGUGCCUCUUGUCUGAGGGACAUAUCAGUGACCUCGACGUUGCCUUUAGACUACAGUUGUGUUAGCCUCUUGCGUAUUGGCUUUUUCAGAGUCAUUUAUGAGCAGAAAAAAAAAAAGUAAAACUUUGCUAAUAUUAACCCUUCUCUAGCUCCUCGAGGGUCUGUGACCUGCAACACAAGGGGUGGGGUCAGGAAAGGGCUGGGGAAGACCUAGCAUUUUUUUUUUCUUUUUUUUUUUUUUUUGAGACGGAGUCUCCCUUUGUCACCCAGGCUGGAGUGGCAUGAUCUCAGCUCACUACAACCUCCACCUCUCGGGUUCAAGCGAUUCUCCUGCCUCAGCCUCCCGAGUAGCUGGGACUAAAAGUGCCCACCACCACACCCAGCUAGUUUUUGUAUUUUUUUUUUUUUUUUUUUGAGACGGAGUCUCGCUCUGUCGCCCAGGCUGGAGUGCAGUGGCGGGAUCUCGGCUCACUGCAAGCUCCGCCUCCCGGGUUCACGCCAUUCUCCUGCCUCAGCCUCCCAAGUAGCUGGGACUACAGGCGCCCGCCACUACGCCCGGCUAAUUUUUUGUAUUUUUAGUAGAGACGGGGUUUCACCGUUUUAGCCGGGAUGGUCUCGAUCUCCUGACCUCGUGAUCCGCCCGCCUCGGCCUCCCAAAGUGCUGGGAUUACAGGCGUGAGCCACUGCGCCCGGCUCCAGCAUUUAUUUCUGAUGUAUCUUUGUGGUAGAAAAUUUGGAAAGUGCAGAGAAGUAUACACAGGAAGAAAAAUUCCCAACCCCCAGAGGCAAACCAGCUGAAACCACGCAACCCCAGUCACCCCAAUGCACCGCGAGGCUGCUGCCUCCUGUCAGGGUCAGAUGAGCCUCGAGGCUCAGGAAAGUCAGAGGAUGCCAUCUGCAUGGUGGUAAAUUACAGAGGUGAUGAGGCAAGGUGGGUGUGGGGCUGUUCUUAAAACGGGGCAGCAGGAAGGCCCCAAGGAGAUGGAUUUGGGCUGGGACGGGAAGAGAGAGCUGGCCAUGCUGGGGUGGGUGGGUGUUCAAAUGGUGGAAACAGCAGACGCAAAGGCCCUGCCGUUGGAACCAGCUUGUGGAAUAAACUUUCAGAAACAGA